CUGCUGUCUCUGCACGGGUGGCCAGAGCCACACAGCCCUUUCUUUAAGUCAGGAGUUGCCCUGUCAGAGCACAAGGCAAGAAGGAAGUGGUAAAGGGACGGAGGGGAAGCCCUGAGAGGACUGAGAGGAUGGGAAAUUCUCUGCUGAGAGAAAACAGGUUUUGCCUUCUCCCAAGAAUCAUGGUGAGCAGCUGAUGGAGAAUAGCUGAAAGGUGGAAAGACUUUACCAAGGAAGGUCUAUAUAAUAGGUUACCACCUAAGAAAUGAAACAACUUUCUGAAAGCCCGGGAAGGAGAUGCUCUCCUGAGCUCCUCAUGCUCCACAAGGAGGUCAAAAUCACCACCCUCUUUCAGCCACUAUUUUAAGUUUGAAAUAAACAGCAAGCUUCCUGCCACCUUGAGUCUUCCUUUGAUGUGCACUCCCUGCAAGCAGGUAAGCAGAGGUCAUCUAGAUUAAAUAGGCACAGAACUCAGAUUUACUUUCUGGACCUCAGCCUCUUUAUUUUAAGUAGAAAUAAUAAUACAAUAUCUACCUUAGAGAGUUCUAGUGUGUAUUGUGCUAGCAUAGUGCCUGACAUAAAGUAGGGUUCAAAAUUAGAAGAUAUUUUCUGCUUUCUUUUUCUGACCAUCAUCUUCCUUAAUAUCAAAGCCGUGCCACCAAAAUAGUGCCACCACAGACAAGGUAAUCUCUAGGGUAUAAAGUGGGGUGAUCUAGAGAGAGUAAGCGAGCCAGAGGGGGUCUUCACAGGGUUAUGUUUGGAAUCCCUGGUCUCAGUUCAUGCUACUGGAGAGUGGAACACAGGAAAAAAUGGUAGCCCACUUUUGACCACUUGCCGAAAAGAGGAUUGGUGGUCCUGUGGAAUAUCUCAUGUCCCUUCCUAAGAAUCAUGUUGUCUGAGACUUCUCUACCCUGGGUUGUCACAGCCCCUUGUCAAUCUUCUACUCUAGCAUUGUUCUAACAAUUAUAUAAAUUACUAUUUUUAUUACUAGAUAUGAGAUGCUCAAAUGUAGUGAUUGUUUCUUAUUUAUCUUUGAAUUCCUGGUUCCUGGCAUUGUUUCUGGCAUAUCACGUGCACUGAAUAAGUGCAAAAAAACUUUAAAAAAAUUUUUUUACUUUAAAAUUUUGUUUUAUGUAAGAAAAAAAACCUUUUUCCAAGGUGCACACAUCUUAUGCUAUUUGGACUUCUUAUGGUUUUUUAUUUAUUUUAAAGAAAAUUCGAUUUUAAAUCUAGAAAGCUUUUUGGUUUCUGCCAUUGCAUUCAUGCUUAAAAUUCUUUGCUCUUCCUAAGAUAAGACAAAUCAACUCACAUAAGUUUUGAUUUUGUUAUUUUACAUUUGGCAACAUAUAUUCAAUAUAUGGUGUCAGAUGUAAAUUUUUUUCCAAAUAGUUGAUCAGUUUGCCCAACAUCUUUAUUUCUAUGAUGAUUUAAAAGGUCUCCCUUGAACCAAGUGCAGUGGCAUGCACCUGUAGUCCCAGCUACUCAGGAGGCUGAGGCAGGAGGAUUGCUUGAGCCCAGGAGUUUGAGGGCAGCCUGAACAACAUAGCAAGACCCAGUCUUAAAAAUAAAUUCAUUAAAAUAAUUAAAUAAAAUGUUUCCGUUAACGUAUUCAAAAGUCUUGUAUAUAUUGGUAUCUAAUUUUCAUUGUCACCCCAACACCCAGUUAUCAUCUAGUCAGCAUACCCCCCCAACCGUGUCUCUCCAGAUCAAAUAAGCUAAGAAGUCAGGGAAAUUUUGCACAGAAUAGAAUGGCACUCAUCCCUUCAUGAGAGGAGCUCAGUCUCAGAGGAAGAGACCUGCCAGCAGCAAACCCAGCUUUUCCCCCUUAGUGGCUGUGGAUCCUCAGACCAGUUGCCUAGCAUUUUGGGCCUCAGUUUCCUCAUUAGUAUAAAAAAUAUAAUGAUAAUAUCUAUCUUAUGGAUUUAUUCUGGGAUUAAAUGAAAUAUAACACACAAAAUGAUUGGCAUAUAGUAAGUAGUGUUUAAGUGUUAGUUUCUUUAUCCUCAUACUCCCAAUUCCCAACAAGUGGGAAGAUGGGUAUACAGAAAUCUAACCCAAACAAUGAACCAAUUUAUUUUCUUUAUUCAAUCCUUUUCUUCUCCUUCUGUCCCUUGUUCUGGGCCUCCAUGCUUUCUGUGAAAGAUGGUGUGAUUUACACAAGACAAAGCCAGUACCUUUCCCCAUUACUUGUGCAUAGCUCCUGGAACUGCACCAAAGAGAUGGUAGCUGAGGACCUCAGGCCUCUCUCUGGACACGGAUACUCUCAAGGGUCAUGACGAGGAUCCCUGGAUAUUUGGGAUCAGAUGAUUUAGGAUCACUUGUUCAUGGAGGUUGGAGAACAUCAGUGGGCUGUUGCUGUGGCAAUGGAGAGCAUGUCAGAUCAAAGGUAGCUUGCGACAUGUGCUUGAGGAAACAGUAUUAACAUGUGUGAGGGCAACCAGUCAAUUUCUGAGUUACACACAAAUAGCAGAAAUGAGGAAAGUCGGAAAAAUUAUGAAAAGAAGUGACAGGCCUGUUUAGGAAAUACUUAGCCUGUUUCUGAUAUGUUGAGUUUCAGGCGGCAGCAGAACACUCAAGAGAUGCCUUGGAAUGUGAGAAUGCAAAGCCCCAAACAGAGAACAUCCAGAUGCUGGGAUCACCAUAUCGCUGAAGGGUGUUUCUGCCUUCCAUGGAAAAAAAUACUCAUUUUUGAAAAGAGGCAAGAUUCCCAAAACGAAAAUGAAAGAAUGUCAUCUACUCCCAUCCAGCAGGACAAUGUUGACCAGACCUACUCAGAGGAGCUGUGCUAUACCCUCAUCAAUCAUCGGGUUCUCUGUACAAGGCCAUCAGGGAACUCUGCUGAAGAGUACUAUGAGAAUGUUCCCUGCAAAGCUGAGAGACCCAGAGAGUCCUUGGGAGGAACUGAGACUGAGUAUUCACUUCUACAUAUGCCUUCUACAGACCCCAGGCAUGCCCGAUCCCCAGAAGAUGAAUAUGAACUUCUCAUGCCUCACAGAAUCUCCUCUCACUUUCUGCAACAGCCACGUCCACUUAUGGCCCCUUCUGAGACUCAGUUUUCCCAUUUAUAGUGAAGUGGCUGGACUAGCAUUUGUUUAGCACCAACAAAUAAAAGGUGGGAUGGGGGAUCUGCCUGAAGCAGGGAUGGGACACAAAGUCCCUCCAGCUUAUCUCCCACAACAACCCUUUCCCUGCAGAGCAUGGUUUGUAUACCACAAGCCCUCUUAGCACGCAAAAGCCAAAAUCUAAAGAUCAACCAUUUAUCCUGAACAACACCAUUUGAGAAAGAGGUAACCAUCUUUGGUUCUACAUGGUUUGGAGAGUAUAGUGGUAGGAGGGGCUCCCUGAUUCCCCUAAAGCUAUGCACACCACAAGGGGCUCUGCUCUUCUGUCUGGGAUCUUCUUAUAAAGUGUUCCCAUGAUCAUUCUCUAAAGUCACAAGGAAGCUUUACUCAUCAUACUAAGUGUGCCCAAGGGGGAGUUCACUCAUUACUGUGACCUUCCAGCUCAGUCCCCACCCAUGGGAGCCUGUGUUGCUCCUCUCACUCCAUGUGUCUAAGUCAUGUCUUUUACAUAGUGUCCUUUGACCUGUUGGCCCCCAUGGUCUGGUUAGUUAUGUGAGUUGAAUCAAGAGGCUCUAGGCCAGAUGUUUACAUAAUUUUAACCUAUAUGAUUUUAUUUUUAACUUUGUAUUUCUCCCUAGAAAUCUUAAUAAGACAAUUAUGCCAUCAGACAAUGUUAAGAAGAACGAUCCUUGGAGAUCCCGUAAUCCCACUACCCUUCUUUGGCUCAGAGAGGAUAAUUUGCCUAAUGAUACAUUAAAGUUAGUGGCAAAACUUAAUUUGGAGCCUGAUUUCCUACUGACUUCCAAUUUAGUGCUCCCCCAGUAUGCUAAAUAGAAAGCCCUCUGCAAUAUAUUAAAUGUAUACUAAAUGUAUAUAUUUAAUAAUGUCAUGUAUAAAAUAUGAAUAAAAUGUCCACAUAGGAAAUUAACACAUAUAUACCUUCUCUGAUAAGCACUCCUCUAUGUGUCCUGAUUAUUUACUUUCUCUUAUCUUUUCCUUAGUGUUCCUCAAAUUAUAUCUAUCCUCUAAACCAGGGAUCAGCAAACUAUAACCCCCAGGCCAAAUCUAGCCCACUCCCUGUUUUUAUAGAUAAAGAUUUGUUGGAACACAGCCACACUCAUUUGUUUACCUACUAUCUAUGAUUGUUCAACCAUGGGAGAGUUGAGUAAUUGUGACAUGGACCAUAGGCCCUAAAGAGCCAAAAUAAAUAUACUUUGGCACUUUUUGGAAAAAAAGUUUGCAGACACCUGCCCUAAAUGAUUAUAGUUUGAGAGAAACUUAACAGAAAUGUGUUUGGUUACUGAUGCAUAAGAGCAAGCACCAAUAAAAUGGCAUAAAAAUAUUAAAUCACAAAUGGAUAAGUGAGACCAAGGCAAUUUAGCAAAUUCUACUAUUUCUGUAUUCACACCUGUGUCUUCCACUUGCUGUUUUAUUUAACUCACGGCUACUGUCCUAAUUUUAGGGAUGCUAAAAUAGUUUGUUUUAAAAGAGGUUUGUUUAAGAAAGCAGUAGGUACAUUAUGUUUACUAGACAGGCCCUUGGACCAGCUAAGCGACAGGGAACCUGGUACAUUAUGUUUAGUUACUGUUUUCUUCUCAAAGUUAACCAAAGCUAAAUAACUUUCCUAUGUAAAAUGUGCUGACUCCCAAAAGAGGAGAAAUGCAAUGGCUUGAGCUUGCAUGUGUCACAGGUUUGUGGAGCCUUCAGCCAGGUGAUGGUCUUCAGCUAAAGAGCCAGCUGCAUCUUGGUAUCUCUUCCUCUGCUAACUUCCUACUUUUAGCAAAAUUCUUUCACUUGGAACUCUAGCUGAUCCUUGGCCAGGAUCAGAUCCUCAAAAGGAAAUAUUCAGUUAGCAGUGGAUAUUGUACAAGAUGUAACAUGGCUUAGAGGAAAGAGUGUAGACCCAGCGACAGAUCAUCAGUCACUCAAAUCCUGGUUCUCUCUCUUCCUCCAUCUGUGACUUUGAACAUGCUACUUGGAGGCUCAGCUUCUUCACCAUCAACAGGAGGAUUACAUCUAAUGCAGGCAAUCAUCUAUUACAGAUGCCGAAUAAAUGAUAUCAAAGAGCAUAGAGAAACAAAAAUCUUUUAUGAUGUACGGAAAAAAACCAUGCUGAUACAGCUGGCUAUUCAGGGUCACCCAGCAGUCCUCCAGCAAGGUAGAAACACCAAAUCAAUGAGUUUAUGCUAGAAUUUUUCACAUGGCCACUGGACCAUUGUGGAAGUAGACUGGUUGAAAUAUUCUUAGUAUGACAUAGUAAGUUAUAUUUGUUUGAACCUUAUCCUGUGAAAGCAUUAUCUGUCCCAAACAGUAUAUGCCUUUUAUCAGGGACACAUUAAAUAUAAAUGUUUAACCAAAGAAAGUUGUUCUUAUAAUGUAAUUAUAACAGGGAUUUAUAAGAGGGAAUUAUAAGAGGGAUUAUGAAAGGGAAUUACUUUUGAGCAAGGGGAGCCAUUUGGGAGUGCUUCAAGAUACCCAAUAUGAUAUACACAAUUAUGAUUUGUCAGUCAAAAAUAAUAUUAAGAACAAAAAAAGAGUUAAAAAAUUCUGAUAUGAGUGUAAUAUACUUAAUAUGUAGGAUGUCUCAAAUUUCCAGUAAAUAAAUUUUAAUGUCCCAAAA